AUGGCUAAAAGACCGGGACCCCCUGGAAGCCGAGAAAUGGGACUGUUGACAUUCAGAGACAUAGCUAUAGAAUUCUCUCUGGCGGAGUGGCAAUGCCUGGAUCAUGCUCAGCAGAAUUUAUAUAGAGAUGUGAUGUUAGAGAACUACAGAAACCUGUUCUCCCUGGGUAUGACUGUCUCUAAGCCAGACUUGAUCGCCUGUCUGGAGCAAAAUAAAGAGCCCCAGAAUAUAAAGAGAAAUGAGAUGGCAGCCAAACACCCAGUUACAUGUUCUCAUUUCAACCAAGACCUUCAGCCAGAGCAGAGCAUAAAAGAUUCACUCCAAAAAGUAAUACCAAGAACAUAUGGAAAAUGUGGACAUGAGAAUUUACAAUUAAAAAAAUGUUGUAAAAGAGUAGAUGAGUGUGAGGUGCACAAAGGAGGUUAUAAUGACCUUAACCAAUGUUUGUCAAAUACCCAAAACAAAAUAUUUCAGACUCAUAAAUGUGUCAAAGUCUUCAGUAAAUUUUCAAAUUCCAAUAGACACAAUGCAAGAUAUACUGGAAAGAAACAUUUGAAAUGUAAAAAAUAUGGCAAAUCAUUUUGCAUGUUUUCACACCUAAAUCAACAUCAGAUAAUUCAUACUAAGGAGAAGUCCUACAAAUGUGAAGAAUGUGGCAAAUCCUUUAACCACUCCUCAAGCGGUACUACACAUAAAAGAAUUCUUACUGGAGAGAAACCCUACAGAUGUGAGGAAUGUGGCAAAGCCUUUAGGUGGCCCUCAAACCUUACUAGACAUAAGAGAAUUCACACUGGAGAGAAACCCUACGCAUGUGAAGAAUGUGGCCAAGCCUUUAGGCGCUCCUCAACACUUACUAACCACAAGAGAAUUCAUACUGGAGAGAGACCCUACAAAUGUGAAGAAUGUGGCAAAGCCUUUAGCGUAUCCUCAGCCCUCAUUUACCACAAGAGAAUUCAUACUGGAGAGAAACCCUACACAUGUGAAGAAUGUGGCAAAGCCUUUAACUGCUCCUCGACUCUUAAGACACAUAAGAUAAUUCAUACUGGAGAGAAACCCUACACAUGUGAAGAAUGUGGCAGAACCUUUAACUGCUCCUCAACUGUAAAGGCACAUAAGAGAAUUCAUACUGGAGAGAAACCAUACAAAUGUGAAGAAUGUGACAAAGCUUUUAAGUGGCAUUCAAGUCUUGCUAAACAUAAGAUAAUUCACACUGGAGAGAAACCCUACAAAUGUAAAUAA